GCCAGUGGACAAAUUCAUAAACAAGAGCUCCAGUUCCCUGGAACCUGAGUCGGGAGACCUGCAGCUCACUUUCUCCCUGUUUGCUGGCCAGCAGGGUUUGUGGCCGCCUCUGCUGUGACGCCACAGCCUGGUGAGGAGGGGGCUGCAGUUCCUCAGGAAACUGCCAGUGGACAAAGUCAUAAACAAGAGUUCCAGUUCCCUGGAACCUGAGUCGGGAGGCCUGCAACUCACUUUCUCCCUGUUUGCUGGCCCAGACAGGCCUGUGCUAGAGGGCUGGAUAGUGUGGUAGUGUGGUGGAUAGAGUGCUGCCUCUAUCCACAACGCAGCCAUAUGCUGACUGAAGAUAACUUUGUGUCUGGAAGAGCCCUCUGAUUUCUUACACUAAUGGCCUUACACGACAUGGAGGAUUUUACAUUUGAUGGAACAAAGCGCUUAAGUGUCAACUACGUGAAGGGAAUUCUUCAACCGACAGACACCUGUGACAUCUGGGAUAAGAUCUGGAACUUCCAAGCCAAGCCUGAUGACCUGCUUAUUUCUACCUAUCCUAAAGCAGGAAUGUACUAUACUAGAUGUCUAUUCAUCUUCAUUUUACGUGCACGUAAGGAACAACAUGGACUCAGGAGAUAGUGGAAUUAAUACAAAAUGAAGGUGAUGUGGAGAAAAGUAAACGGGCACCGACUCAUCAACGAUUUCCUUUCCUCGAAAUGAAAAUCCCAUCCUUAGGAUCUGGUUUGGAACAAGCUCAUGCAAUGCCCUCACCACGGAUCCUGAAAACACAUCUUCCCUUUCACUUGCUGCCACCAUCCUUGCUAGAGAAAAACUGUAAGAUAAUCUAUGUAGCAAGAAAUCCCAAGGACAACAUGGUGUCCUAUUACCAUUUCCAAAGAAUGAAUAAAGCUCUUCCUGCUCCAGGAACAUGGGAAGAGUAUUUUGAGACUUUUCUGGCUGGGAAAGUGUGCUGGGGCUCCUGGCAUGAACAUGUGAAAGGAUGGUGGGAAGCCAAAGACAAACACCGUAUUCUCUAUCUCUUCUAUGAGGACAUGAAGAAGAACCCAAAGCAUGAAAUUCAGAAGCUGGCAGAAUUUAUUGGGAAGAAAUUAGAUGACAAAGUUCUAGAUAAAAUUGUCCAUUACACUUCGUUUGAUGUCAUGAAACAGAAUCCAAUGGCAAACUAUUCAUCGAUUCCUGCUGAAAUCAUGGACCACUCCAUUUCUCCAUUCAUGAGAAAAGGGGCAGUGGGAGACUGGAAGAAACACUUCACCGUGGCUCAGAAUGAGAGAUUUGAUGAAGAUUACAAGAAGAAAAUGACUGAUACCAGACUAACUUUCCACUUCCAGUUCUAGUAAGGAAGAAAAACUGAAAAUGUUUUAGUUUAUUACCCAGUAUAUUUGGGUAAUAAUGAAAGUUUAAUUCUCAUAACAAAUGAUAUCAGAUUCCAGUUAUCAGAAUAGUUUACUGUGUUUGCUCUUAUUCACUCUACUAAAAAAUUAUUUUAAAAGGCUGGAGGCAAGGUGGUGACAGGCAGCAGGGUGGCGACAUGGAGAGAGGGAAGCUCAAUAAAUCACUAGGUACAAUCCUGGUAUCAUUGCCAAUUAUCAUCAUAUUUACAUUUUCUACAAUCAUGUGCUUAUUAACAUAUUGGAAAUGCUUCAGUCCUCACAUGAUAAUACACUAACAUUUUCAGAUUAAGUUUUGGUUCAAGUUAAUUUUUUUUUUUUUUUUUUUGAGACGGAGUCUCGCUCUGUCGCCCAGGCUGGAGUGCAGUGGCACGAUCUCGGCUCACUGCAAGCUCUGCUUCCUGGGUUCACGCUAUUCCCCUGCCUCAGCCUCCCGAGUAGCUGGGACUAUGGGCGCCCACCACCACUCCCGGCUAAUUUUUUUUUUUGUAUUCUUAGUAGAGACGAGGUUUCACCGUGUUAGCCAGGAUGUUCUCGAUCUCCUGACCCCAUGAUCCACCCGCUUCGGCCUCCCAAAGUGCUGAGAUUACAGGCGUGAGCCACUGCGCCCAGCCGGUUCAAGUUAAUUUUUAAAUGCAUCACUAACGUGUAAAUAGUGACUGUUUGUUCCAGCAAUUUUUUGGUGGUGAAGUAACCAUCAAGUGAUUCAGGUUCCUCUUGGAACCCUCCAAGAAAAACUUCAGGGUCCUAGUGUAAUACAUCUGUCCCCAUCUCUCACUGGCGUAUAUAUUUAACUGGACUCACUCUCCCACCCUCAGCUAAUGCUACAAUCCUGGAGUCACCUCUUGACUCAUCUUUCCCAUUGCCACCACAAUCCAUUCUAAUAUGUCAGAAAAUCUGUCAGUUUUAAUCUACGAAAUCUCUUAAAAUAUUUCCGUCUAACCAUUCCUUGUUUUCCUUCUAUUUCUAUAGCCACCCUUCUGGUUCACAAACCUUUUACUUCUUGCCUCAACUAGUGUAAUAGCUUCCUAACCCAUUUCUCUCUAUUUCAGACAGAUGGCAAGGUUAUUUUCCUUAAAAAGACUCUUAUUAUGUUGUUCCUUAGCUCAAAAUCCUUCAAUGGCUGAACUUUCACUGCCUGAAAGAUAAAUCCCAAGAUUUUAGCCAUGCAUUCAAGAGCAGCUAUAACCAUAAUGACUCCAGCCUUCACACUUCCAGCUUCACCUUCCAAACCACCUCCAUAUUCCAGCAAAUUAGCCUACUUACUGGGUCCUAGUCACAUCUUACCACUUCCUACCCUCCCAGUUUUAUUUAUACCAAGCCUCCUCCUGAAAUUUCUCUUCCUUUCUUUCUACCUACCCAAGACAUACCACGUGCUUCAAUAACCAGUCCCUUCCUCCUACAAACACUACAACCUGGAAAGCACUCUUGCUUUUCUGAAGUCCUCUAUACUUAGUGUAACUCUUCUGUGAUGAAGAUUAAAGUGUAUUAUGGCAACUCUCA